GCCAGCGCCUGCGCACUGAGGGCGGCCUGGUCGUCGUCUGCGGCGGCGGCGGCGGCUGAGGAGCCCGGCUGAGGCGCCAGUACCCGGCCCGGUCCGCAUUUCGCCUUCCGGCUUCGGUUUCCCUCGGCCCAGCACGCCCCGGCCCCGCCCCAGCCCUCCUGAUCCCUCGCAGCCCGGCUCCGGCCGCCCGCCUCUGCCGCCGCAAUGAUGAUGAUGGCGCUGAGCAAGACCUUCGGGCAGAAGCCCGUGAAGUUCCAGCUGGAGGACGACGGCGAGUUCUACAUGAUCGGCUCCGAGGUGGGAAACUACCUCCGUAUGUUCCGAGGUUCUCUGUACAAGAGAUACCCCUCACUCUGGAGGCGACUAGCCACUGUGGAAGAGAGGAAGAAAAUAGUUGCAUCGUCACAUGGUAAAAAAACAAAACCUAACACUAAGGAUCACGGAUACACGACUCUAGCCACCAGUGUGACCCUGUUAAAAGCCUCGGAAGUGGAAGAGAUUCUGGAUGGCAACGAUGAGAAGUACAAGGCUGUGUCCAUCAGCACAGAGCCCCCCACCUACCUCAGGGAACAGAAGGCCAAGAGGAACAGCCAGUGGGUACCCACCCUGCCCAACAGCUCCCACCACUUAGAUGCCGUGCCAUGCUCCACAACCAUCAACAGGAACCGCAUGGGCCGAGACAAGAAGAGAACCUUCCCCCUUUGGUGUGGAUGCAUCGCUGCACUCACCCUCCGUGCUGAUUCCGCCUUAGUUCUCCACUUUGAUGACCAUGACCCAGCUGUGAUCCAUGAGAACGCAUCUCAGCCCGAGGUGCUGGUCCCCAUCCGGCUGGACAUGGAGAUCGAUGGGCAGAAGCUGCGAGACGCCUUCACCUGGAACAUGAAUGAGAAGUUGAUGACGCCUGAGAUGUUUUCAGAAAUCCUCUGUGACGAUCUGGAUUUGAACCCGCUGACGUUUGUGCCAGCCAUCGCCUCUGCCAUCAGACAGCAGAUCGAGUCCUACCCCACGGACAGCAUCCUGGAGGACCAGUCAGACCAGCGCGUCAUCAUCAAGCUGAACAUCCAUGUGGGAAACAUUUCCCUGGUGGACCAGUUUGAGUGGGACAUGUCAGAGAAGGAGAACUCACCAGAGAAGUUUGCCCUGAAGCUGUGCUCGGAGCUGGGGUUGGGCGGGGAGUUUGUCACCACCAUCGCAUACAGCAUCCGGGGACAGCUGAGCUGGCAUCAGAAGACCUACGCCUUCAGCGAGAACCCUCUGCCCACAGUGGAGAUUGCCAUCCGGAACACGGGCGAUGCGGACCAGUGGUGCCCACUGCUGGAGACUCUGACAGACGCUGAGAUGGAGAAGAAGAUCCGCGACCAGGACAGGAACACGAGGCGGAUGAGGCGUCUUGCCAACACGGCCCCGGCCUGGUAACCAGCCCAUCAGCACACGGCUCCCACGGAGCAUCUCAGAAGAUUGGGCCGCCUCUCCUCCAUCUUCUGGCAAGGACAGAGGCGAGGGGACAGCCCAGCGCCAUCCUGAGGAUCGGGUGGGGGUGGAGUGGGGGCUUCCAGGUGGCCCUUCCCGGCACACAUUCCAUUUGUUGAGCCCCAGUCCUGCCCCCCACCCCACCCUCCCUACCCCUCCCCAGUCUCUGGGGUCAGGAAGAAACCUUAUUUUAGGUUGUGUUUUGUUUUUGUAUAGGAGCCCCAGGCAGGGCUAGUAACAGUUUUUAAAUAAAAGGCAACAGGUCAUGUUCAAUUUCUUCAACAGGUCAUGUUCAAUUUCUUCAAAGUUUUAACAUAAAAAUAAUGAGAGCCAGGAGUGGGGCCGGGGCCUGGGGGGACGAAGGUGGUAUGUGAACAAGGUUGGCACACAGGCCUCACCCUCCUCUGCCUCAGAUUCCCAAGUGGGCAGGUGGGGGUGAAUGGGGCUCCGGGUAGCACCUCAGCUCCUCUCAGCUCCCCUCAGCCUGUUCUCCUUCCAGACCCAGAGAGCUGAGAAGAGUAGCUGUGAGGCUCAGGGCAAGAGGCUCUCUGCCUUUCAGGAACAGCCCUAACCCUGCUCCCCUUGCUUGGCCUCAGGAAGGUGCCGCGAGCUCUCCUGCCGUCCCUGGGCCGCCCUGGCUCUGCUGUGUCCAGAUGGUCAGGCUACUGCCAGCUGGGGCCUUGCUGCUCUGAAGUCCCCUGCGGAGGGCCCAGUCCUGUGUGGGCACUGCUGGGCUGUCGCCAGCCUGGGUGCAGGAGGGCUGUUCUAGCUCCAGUGGCACCCAUAGCCAGGUCAGCUGGGGCCCUUUCCCACCCCAGCAGGUGCUGUGGCCUGGGCCAGCUCCUGCCUUACAAGCCAGCUGUGAGGAAUAUGGGAAUAGCCCUCCCGGCCUGGUGCCAGCUCUUGGAGUUGACACGGUACAGGGAGGAGACACAGCCCAGGGUCCCUUCCCAGCCCUGCCUCCAAGGAGUUCAUGUCCCCUCUGUUCUCAUCUGUAAUAGGGAGGUGUCCCCAUUCUUCAGAAUGGACACAGGAUCUGGGAGGGCAGCAAACUGGCUCGCAGCUCCAGCCUUACUGAAGAGAAUGGGCACAGAUCCGGGCACAGAUCCCAGCACAGACUGCUGCCACCCUCAGCUGUUGGCAGGUCCCAUGCUGCCAGGGCAGGGCUAGGGUCAGAGGCUGCUGUGCUCCCUGGAAGUGGGGUAGGGCCCCAUGUGGGGCAGAGGCAGAGCUCUGAUUAGGGAUUGGGGUUCUUGGUCGCUGAGAUGUGAGAGGAGGGCUCCUUUGAGCACAUGUUAGCAUGGGACUCUUCCCAGGGAGUUUGCACUCAGGGCCUCUGCCCUCCAUCAAAGAGUGGAACUCCCCAGAGCCCCAUGCACAGCAAGGGGACAGCUGGGCCUUACUGGAAGGCCUUGAACAAAGGGGAAGAUUCCCAGCCCAGCUGCUCUUAGACAUGAACAGGUUUCAUUGCUGAGGUGUUUGUUCUGUCCAUGAGGUAGGAACCUCGGCAAUGAAAGGGUGAGGCAGCCCUGUGUCUCCACAACUGGGGGGAUGGAAGGAACCUUGGCUGCCUCACCCCACAGGUCGGGCAGGGCCACCUGGCUGGGAGGUGCCGGGAAGGCUGGGCCCUCACUCCUGACCGCCAGCUCACACCGCCGCAAAGCCAUCUCCACAAGGUCUGGCUACAACACGGAGGGCAGACUCAACAGAGAACAGUGUUGUUACCAUGAAAAUGACAACCUGUCUUUGGAGGAGGCCCCGUGCCACUGAGCAUCCAGAAAUAAACCACAACAUGGACAGGCUUAGAACAACAAGGAAAGCUGCCAGGUCAGAAGAGAAAAAUGAGCCACAGGGGUCGGAUAAGGCUCACACACGUCCUCAGCUAAAAAGGGCAGGAACAGAACCUUCCAGAAGUCCCUGCCUCACCCAGUCUCAGAACUCUGCUAAGGUGAAAACUUAGGCUCUGAGGUCAUAGAAAGGGCAGAAGACCUAGUCCUGGCCCUCUUCUGCACCUGAAUCCAUGGGGCUUUGGCAUCACCAGAUGAAAAAUGAGGCAUACGCCCACCUGUCAGGGUGGCUGAUGAGAGACAGGAGAGGCUAGAUUGGCAUCAGCCUGAAGGCACCACUGGCAGGAACAUCUGUAGGCUGGUUUGGCACAACCUAGGAGACGCCUGUCCUGGCCCCAGCAGCCGAAAUCUGGUGAACUUCCCCGCUGACUGGCAGGUAGCAGAGGCCUAUGGUGGGCAGGACUUGCCCAAGGCCCUGGUGGGGCCAGGAUGAGAACCCUGAGCCUGUCACCUGUGAGCUCAAAAGCUCUGCCUGGCAACCUGUGAGCUCAAAGCUCUGCCAGGCAACCAUGGGCAGUUUCUUUGCCCUCUGUGGGCACCCCUAUCCUACCACCUGCAGUUGGGCUGAGAGGCCACACUGAGUGAGGACGGGGCAGGCAUAGAAGGAUGUGGCCAGGUGAGAUGGGGAAGCCAGUGCUGUGGGCCAAGAGACUGCAGCUCAUUCUGUUUAUUCAGGUGGGCCCUUGCAUGGGCCCAGCCUUUAGGAUGGGUUUUUUCUGCCCCAAGUAGGGGUCAUGGGUAGGAUGGAAGCUGCCAGAAGCCUCUUAGGCCUGGCCCUGGGUGGGGGUCACUGCUGCGGGGGUGGCAGAUGGGGUCCUGGCUGUUCCUCAGGGAGGGGCAGGUAAUUGGGGUCUUCUGCAGGGGCAUCCAGGAGCAGCUUUCUGUGGGGAGGGGCCCGUGUUGAGCACAGGCCAGCACAGGUCCCCAUCGGUGGGGAUCCUUCUGAGGGUGGGGAGAGGGAGGGAGGGCUCUCAACACUCACAGGAAGCCAGGGGUCUGCAGGAGCCUCUUGCCUCCAGGCUGGUUGGGGAAGACGUCCUCCAGGAAGUAGUAGAUAUGGCCCACCGCAAUCCCUGUGAGACAGCCACGGACUGUGGGGUCACCCUCCACAGCCCAGAGUCCUAGACCAGCAGAGCCUGCCCCAGGCCCCCAUCCACAGCCUGGUGGCCCUGCAGGCCCCACAGCAUGAGUGCCCCAAAGCCUUGCACAGAGUGCCAGCCCCGGGUUGGCCGUGAAGGACAAGCUUAAAAGGCCCAGAAGCAGGCAGGACCCAGGGAGGGGAGGGCCUGAGAAUAGUGGAGGAGUGGGAGCCAUGGGGCAGGAACCCUGACCCUCCCAUCCUCACUCCCAUCAGGACCGUGCAAGCAUCAGUAGAUCCGUCCUGACGAUGCAAAUUAUGUGGGCCGGCUGGCUUGAGGGGCUGUAAGAGCACAGCAGCUGGGAGGGCAGGAAGAUGGGGAUGGAGCCAGGUGUGAGGAGAACUCCAGCAAGGAUGGGAGAGGGGCCCCAGGGCAUAAGCAGCGUGUCCUGAGGGGAGUGGCCAGCCUGGGGCGGACUAGAUGUACCGGGAGGCUCACCCAGCAGGUCCACGAGGAUGGAGUUGCCCAGCAGCAGCGAGAAGCCCAUGAGCGCCCAAGGCAGGAACGGUGCCUGGAAAGUGAGCAGGCCGAAGAAGUUGACCCUCACCCGAGGGCUGCGGCGGCUCCACACGUACACCAGCAUGGCCAUGAGGGCCUGGCCCAGGAAGAACAGGCUGCCCAGGAGUCCCAGCAGCUGGGCCAGAGUCAAGGUGCUCCGGUGCAGGCCUCAGCCCAAGCCCAGGGCCCCUCUGACUUCCCAAGACCCUGGAAUUCUUCCCCUCAUCUCCCCUAUGUGCUAUUCCCUCAUCAAGAUGAGCCAGUCCAAUAAAGGCGACACACUCCACGGGC